GCAGACACCCAGCCACUCUGAGCAGAACUGACAGCAUGAAGGUACGGGGCCCAGGGUCGGGGGACUCAUAGCAUGGGGGAACUGAGCCCACUCCAGAGGCCCCUGGCCACAGAGGGCACUAUGAAGGCACAAGGAGUUCUCUUGAAACUCGCACUCCUGGCCCUGCCGCUGCUGCUGCUUCUCUCCACGCCCCCGUGUGCCCCCCAGGUCUCCGGGAUCCGAGGAGAUGCUCUGGAGAGGUUUUGCCUUCAGCAACCCCUGGACUGUGACGACAUCUAUGCCCAGGGCUACCAGUCAGACGGCGUGUACCUCAUCUACCCCUCGGGCCCCAGUGUGCCUGUGCCCGUCUUCUGUGACAUGACCACCGAGGGCGGGAAGUGGACGGUUUUCCAGAAGAGAUUCAAUGGCUCAGUAAGUUUCUUCCGCGGCUGGAAUGACUACAAGCUGGGCUUCGGCCGUGCUGAUGGAGAGUACUGGCUGGGGCUGCAGAACAUGCACCUCCUGACACUGAAGCAGAAGUAUGAGCUGCGAGUGGACUUGGAGGACUUUGAGAACAACACGGCCUAUGCCAAGUACGCUGACUUCUCCAUCUCCCCGAACGCGGUCAGCGCAGAGGAGGAUGGCUACACCCUCUUUGUGGCAGGCUUUGAGGAUGGCGGGGCAGGUGACUCCCUGUCCUACCACAGUGGCCAGAAGUUCUCUACCUUCGACCGGGACCAGGACCUCUUUGUGCAGAACUGCGCAGCUCUCUCCUCAGGAGCCUUCUGGUUCCGCAGCUGCCACUUUGCCAACCUCAAUGGCUUCUACCUAGGUGGCUCCCACCUCUCUUAUGCCAAUGGCAUCAACUGGGCCCAGUGGAAGGGCUUCUACUACUCCCUCAAACGCACUGAGAUGAAAAUCCGCCGGGCCUGAAGGGCUGGCCCCCUCAGGCACCUUUCCUCCCCUGGACACCCAUGGUCUCCAUGAGUGCUCCCUCUGCUGCCCCUGAUGCAUGCUUCUGCUGAUUCCCGAGCACCAACUCCUUACAAGGGGGCCUUGUGGCUCUCAGCCAUGCCACAUCCCUGUCACACACCCAGGGCAUCCAUUCCUAAGCCAGACCCGGCUCCCCUACACCUGAAGUUACACUGCCAGCAGUUCCCCAGGCCUCUUCCGAGAGGCACAUGGUUCUAGCCUGGACCUGGCUGGGCUCCAUGAGAAUGAGUUGCCUCCAACCUGUCCCAACAGCUGACAGCCAGGAGCCACUCUCCCAGCUGCAGGCCUUUGUGGUCCAUCUUGUCCUGCUUCCUCACUGUGGACCCCUGUCUGGGCCACCCUAGUGUGCUAAGCUGAGCAGUGCAGUGUGAACAGGGCCCAUGGUGUAUUCUAGGCCACAGCCCAGCACUCCUCUGGGCUGCUCUCAAACCAUGUCCCAUCUUCAGCAUCCCUCCCACCAACUUACUCCCCUGUGGUGAGUACCGUGGAACCCCAGCCCACCUCACUAUCAUACUCAGCUUCCCCUGAUGGCCCAUCCCAGCCCCUGAAGCUCUAUGCCAAGAACACAGCUACCGCACACCACCCUGAAACAGCCACAGCCAAGGUAGGCAUGCAUAUGAGGUCUUCCCCAUACCCUCUGGGUGUUGAGAGGUUUAGCCACAUGAGGGAGCAGAGGACAAUCUCUGCAGGGCUGGGAGUGGGUAGGGACUGAAGGUCUCAAUAAACCUUCAGAACCUGAAUGAACUGGCUUCAUACACACAAACAUAUUUGUUUAUCCCCCAAAUGUAGGCACCUGGCUCCUCCUUGCUCCCCUGCUGAUGGUGUCCUACCCCGAACUCCAAAAAUUACACCUGGAGUCAGGUGCAGAAGGGAACCUUGUAUUUCACAGGCCUCAUUUUGAUGGCAAAAAGACAGUGUAAUAAUAACAUAAUAAUAAUAAAAAUAUAAUACUGAAAA